GACCUGUAAGUUGCCUAGGACAGUGGCCUGGUCCCAGGGGCUGUUGUGGGGAGUUGAAGAACACCCUGGCCUCCUCCAUCAUGUCGGCCAAGAGGGCAGAAUUGAAGAAAACACAUCUGAGCAAGAACUACAAGGCAGUUUGCCUGGAAUUGAAGCCAGAGCCGACCAAAACAUUUGAUUACAAAGCAGUUAAACAAGAAGGGCGGUUUACCAAAGCAGGAGUGACACAGGACCUAAAGAAUGAACUCAGGGAAGUGAGAGAAGAGCUCAAGGAGAAAAUGGAGGAGAUAAAACAGAUAAAGGAUCUAAUGGACAAGGAUUUUGAUAAACUUCACGAAUUUGUGGAAAUUAUGAAGGAAAUGCAGAAAGAUAUGGAUGAGAAGAUGGACAUUUUAAUAAAUACACAGAAGAACUAUAAGCUUCCCCUUAGAAGAGCACCAAAGGAGCAGCAGGAACUCAGGCUGAUGGGAAAGACUCACAGAGAACCACAGCUCAGGCCCAAGAAAAUGGAUGGAGCCAGUGGAGUCAAUGGAGCACCCUGUGCUCUUCACAAGAAGACGAUGGCACCACAAAAAACAAAACAGGGCUCACUGGAUCCCCUUCAUCACUGUGGGACCUGCUGCGAGAAAUGUUUGUUGUGUGCUCUAAAGAACAACUACAAUCGGGGGAACAUUCCUUCAGAGGCCUCAGGCCUUUACAAAGGUGGAGAGGAGCCAGUGACCACCCAACCUUCUGUGGGCCACGCUGUGCCUGCCCCAAAGUCCCAGACUGAGGGAAGGUGAAGCUUAACUGCCAGCUUGAAAUGAGAGUAAAGAAGAUACAGAGCAAACAGUGUUUCAGAAACUGUCCUGCCCUGGGUGUGAUUCUUUGGCUUCAAUUUGAAGGACGAGGAAUGAUGGGAUUUCAUAUUUUAUUUCACACCAGUUCCUCCUUGUUUCAUCUCUUUGCUAAGCUGGCUGCUUCUACCAUCUAAUAAAUAAUUGGCCAAGUUC